GAGACUGUAGAAGAGAGAGCAAUUGGCCAAUGAGGACUGCGGGGCGGGACCCUGUGCCGCGGCGGAGUCCAAGAUGGCGGCGUGCGGUUCCGCUGUGUGAAACGAGCGCGGGGCGGCGGGUUACUCAGCUCCGCGGAGACGACCUCCGACGACCCGCAACAAUGAAGGGAAAAGAGCGCUCGCCAGUGAAGGCCAAACGCUCCCGUGGUGGUGAGGACUCGACUUCCCGCGGUGAGCGGAGCAAGAAGUUAGGGGGCUCUGGUGGCAGCAAUGGGAGCAGCAGCGGAAAGACCGAUAGCGGCGGUGGGUCGCGGCGGAGUCUCCACCUGGACAAGUCCAGCAGUCGAGGUGGCAGCCGCGAGUAUGAUACCGGUGGGGGCAGCUCCAGUAGCCGCUUGCAUAGUUAUAGCUCCCCGAGCACCAAAAAUUCUUCGGGCGGGGGCGAAUCGCGCAGCAGCUCCCGGGGUGGAGGCGGGGAGUCACGUUCCUCUGGGGCCGCCUCCUCAGCUCCCGGCGGCGGGGACGGCGCGGAAUACAAGACUCUGAAGAUAAGCGAGUUGGGGUCCCAGCUUAGUGACGAAGCGGUGGAGGACGGCCUGUUUCAUGAGUUCAAACGCUUCGGUGAUGUAAGUGUGAAAAUCAGUCAUCUGUCGGGUUCUGGCAGCGGGGAUGAGCGGGUAGCCUUUGUGAACUUCCGGCGGCCAGAGGACGCGCGGGCGGCCAAGCAUGCCAGAGGCCGCCUGGUGCUCUAUGACCGGCCUCUGAAGAUAGAAGCUGUGUAUGUGAGCCGGCGCCGCAGCCGCUCCCCUUUAGACAAAGAUACUUAUCCUCCAUCAGCCAGUGUGGUCGGGGCCUCUGUAGGUGGUCACCGGCACCCCCCUGGAGGUGGUGGAGGCCAGAGAUCACUUUCCCCUGGUGGCGCUGCUUUGGGAUACAGAGACUACCGGCUGCAGCAGUUGGCUCUUGGCCGCCUGCCCCCUCCACCUCCGCCACCAUUGCCUCGAGACCUGGAGAGAGAAAGAGACUACCCGUUCUAUGAGAGAGUGCGCCCUGCAUACAGUCUUGAGCCAAGGGUGGGAGCUGGAGCAGGUGCUGCUCCUUUCAGAGAAGUGGAUGAGAUUUCACCCGAGGAUGAUCAGCGAGCUAACCGGACGCUCUUCUUGGGCAACCUAGACAUCACUGUAACGGAGAGUGAUUUAAGAAGGGCGUUUGAUCGCUUUGGAGUCAUCACAGAAGUAGAUAUCAAGAGGCCUUCUCGCGGCCAGACUAGUACUUACGGCUUUCUCAAAUUUGAGAACUUAGAUAUGUCUCACCGGGCCAAAUUAGCAAUGUCUGGCAAAAUUAUAAUUCGGAAUCCUAUCAAAAUUGGUUAUGGUAAAGCUACACCCACCACCCGCCUCUGGGUGGGAGGCCUGGGACCUUGGGUUCCUCUUGCUGCCCUGGCACGAGAAUUUGAUCGAUUUGGCACCAUACGCACCAUAGACUACCGAAAAGGUGAUAGUUGGGCAUAUAUCCAGUAUGAAAGCCUGGAUGCAGCGCAUGCUGCCUGGACCCAUAUGCGGGGCUUCCCACUUGGUGGCCCAGAUCGACGCCUUAGAGUAGACUUUGCCGACACCGAACAUCGUUACCAGCAGCAGUAUCUGCAGCCUCUGCCCUUGACUCAUUAUGAGCUGGUGACAGAUGCUUUUGGACAUCGGGCACCAGACCCUUUGAGGGGUGCUCGGGAUAGGACACCACCCUUACUAUACAGAGAUCGUGAUAGGGACCUUUAUCCUGACUCUGAUUGGGUGCCACCCCCACCCCCAGUCCGAGAACGCAGCACUCGGACUGCAGCUACUUCUGUGCCUGCUUACGAGCCACUGGAUAGCCUAGAUCGCAGGCGGGAUGGUUGGUCCUUGGACCGGGACAGAGGUGAUCGAGAUCUGCCCAGCAGCAGAGACCAGCCUAGGAAGCGAAGGCUGCCUGAGGAGAGUGGAGGACGUCAUCUGGAUAGGUCUCCUGAGAGUGACCGCCCACGAAAACGUCACUGCGCUCCUUCUCCUGACCGCAGUCCAGAAUUGAGCAGUAGCCGGGAUCGUUACAACAGCGACAAUGAUCGAUCUUCCCGUCUUCUCUUGGAAAGGCCCUCUCCAAUCAGAGACAGACGAGGUAGUUUGGAGAAGAGCCAGGGUGACAAGCGAGACCGUAAAAACUCUGCAUCAGCUGAACGAGAUAGGAAGCACCGGACAACUGCUCCCACUGAGGGAAAAAGCCCUCUGAAAAAAGAAGACCGCUCUGAUGGGAGUGCACCUAGCACCAGCACUGCUUCCUCCAAGCUGAAGUCCCCGUCCCAGAAACAGGAUGGGGGGACAGCCCCUGUGGCAUCAGCCUCUCCCAAACUCUGUUUGGCCUGGCAGGGCAUGCUUCUACUGAAGAACAGCAACUUUCCUUCCAACAUGCAUCUGUUGCAGGGUGACCUCCAAGUGGCUAGUAGUCUUCUUGUGGAGGGUUCAACUGGAGGCAAAGUGGCCCAGCUCAAGAUCACUCAGCGUCUCCGUUUGGACCAGCCCAAGUUGGAUGAAGUAACUCGACGCAUCAAAGUAGCAGGGCCCAAUGGUUAUGCCAUUCUUUUGGCUGUGCCUGGAAGUUCUGACAGCCGGUCCUCCUCUUCCUCAGCUGCAUCAGACACUGCCACUUCUACUCAGAGGCCACUUAGGAACCUUGUGUCCUAUUUAAAGCAAAAGCAGGCAGCCGGGGUGAUCAGCCUCCCUGUGGGGGGCAACAAAGACAAGGAAAACACCGGGGUCCUUCAUGCCUUCCCACCUUGUGAGUUCUCCCAGCAGUUCCUGGAUUCCCCUGCCAAGGCACUGGCCAAAUCUGAAGAAGAUUACCUGGUCAUGAUCAUUGUCCGUGGGUUUGGUUUUCAGAUAGGAGUUAGGUAUGAGAACAAGAAGAGAGAAAACUUGGCGCUGACCCUGUUAUAGUGGUUAUAGUGGUGUCCCUAAAGGGAGGAAAUGAUUUCAGCAAAACUGGUUGAACAGCGGAUGAAGAUAUGGAAUUCAAAGCUCUAAUGGACCUUUUUGAAGAGAAGUUGUGGCUUAUGUGGAGUUUACAUGGGCCUCUGAUGGAAGAAAGCUAAUCUGUUUAGUAUUUGUGCAUUUUACUAAAAUGGCAGCUUAAAGUUGUGUAUCUGCUAUUGUGAUGCCAAUGCCGGUGUUUUAAGUGGAAAAAAAAUGACCUCUUUGAUUUGUGCUGUGUACACAAGAUUUCUGGAAAAGUAAAGAAAAACCCUUUUUAUGGCUCACACAGCUUAAGAGUAGCUGUCUCUCAAACGUGCGCUCACAGUUGAGCUGCUUUUGUUUUAUUCUAAAUAAAUUGUUUCUUUUGAGGAAAA